AGGGCCGCUCGCAGGAGGCCGGGAACAUGGCGGGGCAGCCCGCGGCCACCGGCUCGCCGUCUGCCGACAAGGACGGAAUGGAGCCCAACGUCGUGGCUCGGAUCUCGCAGUGGGCAGACGACCACCUGCGCCUAGUCCGGGGACACGGUAUUCCUCUCUGGCCCAAGCUGGAGUGCAGUGGCACGAUCAUAGCUCACUGCUGCUGCUCCACCCACUUCGGCCGAAAAGAUCCUCCCACUUCAGCCUCCCGAGUAGCUGGAACCACAGAACAUCAGCACUGGAAUGGCCAUAGCUGGAAUAAUGUUACUUUUGAGAAGCAUUCGACUGACAUCAAAAUUUACAAGCUCUUCGGAUAUUCCAGUAGAAUUUAUAAGAAGAAAUGUUAAACUACGUGGACGAUUACGCCGAAUAACUGAGAAUGGUUUAGAAAUUGAACAUAUACCUAUUACUUUACCUAUUAUAGCUUCAUUGAGAAAAGAGCCACGUGGUGCUUUGCUGGUUAAGUUGGCUGGAGUAGAACUCGCUGAAACUGGGAAGGCAUGGUUACAAAAAGAGCUAAAACCUUCCCAAUUACUAUGGUUCCAACUUCUUGGAAAGGAGAAUUCAGCACUCUUUUGCUAUCUUCUGGUGAGUAAGGGUGGAUAUUUCAGCGUGAAUCUGAAUGAAGAAAUUUUGAGAAGAGGCCUUGGCAAAACUGUUCUUGUUAAAGGGCUUAAAUAUGAUUCUAAAAUCUACUGGACAGUUCACAGAAACUUACUUAAAGCUGAAUUAACAGCCUUAAAAAAAGGAGAAGGAAUAUGGAAGGAAGACUCUGAAAAAGAAAGUUACUUAGAAAAAUUCAAAGAUUCCUGGAGAGAAAUAUGGAAAAAGGACAGUUUUUUAAAAACAACAGGAUCAGAUUUCAGCUUGAAAAAAGAAAGUUAUUAUGAAAAACUUAAAAGGACUUAUGAAAUAUGGAAAGACAACAUGAACAACUGCUCCUUAAUACUGAAGUUCAGAGAACUUAUAAGUCGCAUAAACUUUCGUAGAAAAGGGUGAAACGGUCAAGAAAUCUAGAGGUAACCUUCUCCAAAGAGUGAAAUAUGUAAAUAUAUGGACGUUUUUCAUUGAAUCAAAAUGGAAGUUUUGCCAAAUGAUCAAAGUGUUAGUCCAAUGGUAUUUAAAUAUUAAAAAGAGAUGAUUAUUAUAAGCAUAAUGUCAGAAUUAAUUUAAACAAAUUAUAAUUAAUGUAAUAUGAUUUUAGGAAGGAUGAAACACUUUAUGAGAAGUUACCAGGCUGAAUGAUUUACAUAUAUAGUGCUAAUGUGUGAAGAGAAAGUUUAACUCUUCACCCACUAUGUUGUUUUUAGUUAUUUUGGGCUGCCAUAUUGAAUUUUUUGUUUGUUUGUUUUGAGAAGGCGUUUCGCUCUUGUUGCCCAGGCUGGAGUGCAAUGGCGUGAUCUUGGCUCACUGCAACCUCCUGCUUCCUGGGUUCAAGCGAUUCUCCUGCCUCAGCCUCCUGAGUAGCUGGGAUUACAGGCAUGCACCACCAUGCCCGGCUAAUUUUGCAUUUUUAGUAGAGACGGGGUUUCUCCAUGUUGGUCAGGCUGGUCUCAAACUCUUGACUUCAGAUGAUCUACCCACCUUGGCAUCCUAAAGUGCUGGGAUUACAGGCGUGAGCUACCAAGCCCGGCUUUUUUUGUUUUGACAUGGAGUUUCGCUCUUGUCACCCAGGCAGGAGUGCAGUGGCGUUAUCUUGGUUCACUGCAACCUCCGCCUCCUGGAUUCAAGUGAUUCUCCUGCCUGAGCCUCCCAAGUACCUGGGAUUACAGGAGCUCCCACCAAGCCUGGCUAAGUUUUGUAUUGCCAUAUUGAAUUUUUGUUUAGAAAAGAUAUGUGUUUAUGUUUCCAGUUUUAUUACCUUUCACUAUUUAUAAUAAAGGAAUUCUUUAUGCUUUA